GAUUACAGGCGUGAGGCACCGCGCCCGGCCCUGUGUGUGAUUUUUCUACCUCUGUUCCUUUGAUUGUUACUUCAGCCUAUAAUGCCUCUUUUCCCUUCAGUUCCUUUUCUAAAUUCUACCUAUUUUUAAAUAUCUAGAUAAUAGUGGUCACUUAUUGUGUGCUUAUUAUUUAAGGUUCUAUUCUAAGUAUUUUAUGUGGAUUAAUUCAUUUAAUCCUCACUGCAGUCCCCUAAGGGACUCAUAUUAUACUUAUUGUACAGAUGAAACUGGAGCACACAGGUUAAACAACUCGCUGGAGAUGAUACAGCUAUUAGGAGUGUUACCUGGGAUAUGAACCCAGGUAGUCUAAUUCCAGAAUCUGUAUUUUUAGCCGUCAUGCUUUACUGCAUCUUACUUUACAGAUAGCCUCCGAAAACACAGCAAGUAGUUUUGAUAACAAAAGACUGAAUAUAAGCAAAGUUGAUCACUAUUUUAGCUGAUGAAGAGAAUUUGCAGUCUUUUGUUUUGCCUUUGUCUCUCCUGAGAAAUAACUUUGUUUUUUAAGUUCUGAAUUACUAUGCUAGGGUUUCUUUUUUUUGAGACGGAGUCUUGCUCUGUCGCCCAGGCUGGAGUGCAGUGGCGUGAUCUUGGCUCACUGCAAGCUCCGCCUCCCAGGUUCUCGCCAUUCUCCUGCCUUAGCCUCCCGAGUAGCUGGGACUACAGGCGCCCGCCACCACGCCCGGCUAAUUUUUUGUAUUUGUAGUAGAGAUGGGGUUUCACCGUGUUAGCCAGGAUGGUCUCAAUCUCCUGACCUCGUGAUCCGCCCGCCUUGGCCUCCCAAAGUGCUGGGAUUAGAGGUGUGAGCCACCGCGCCCGGUCUGUGCUAGGGUUUUAAAAAUUGAGGGUUUUUUUUUUUUUUUUUCCCGAGAUGGAGUCUUGCUCUAUUGCCCAGGCUGGAGUGCAGUGGCAUGAUCUCAGCUCGCUGCAACGUCCGCCUCCCAGGUUCAAGCAAUUCUCUGCCUCAGCCUCCUGAGUAGCUGGGAUUACAGGUGCCUGCCACCACGCCCGGCUAAUUUUUUUGUAUUUUUAGUAGAGACGGGGUUUCACCAUCUUGGCCAGGCUGGUCUUGAACUCCUGACCUUGUGAUCCACCUGCCUCAGCCUCCCAAAGUGCUGGGAUUAUAGGUGUGAGCCACCGCGCCUGGACAAAAAUUGAGUUUUUAAAUCAUUCAUUACUUGGUCACAUCAGGAGUAGGAGUACCUGCAUCAGAGUGGUACAUCAGAGUGGUACACUUAUUUAUUUAUUUAUUUAAUAUCUUUUUUGAGACGGAGUUUCGCUCUUGUUGCCCGAGCUGGUGUGCAGUGGUGCAAUCUUGGCUCACUGCAACCUCCACCUCUCAGGUUCAAGCAAUUCUCCUGCCUCAGCCUCCCAAGUAGCUGGGAUUACAGGUGCGCACCACCAUGCCUGGCUAAUUUUUUGUAUUUUAGUAGAAACGAGAUUUUACCAUGUUAGCCAGGCUGGUCUUGAACUCCUGACCUCAGGUGAUCCGCCUGCCUUGGCCUCCCAAAGUGUUGGGAUUAUAGGCAUGAGCUGCCACGCCCAGCUAUUUAUUUUUACAAAUGGGGUCUCACUAUGUUGUCCAGGCUGGACUUGAACUCCUGGGUUCAAGUGAUCCUCCUGCCUCAGCCUCCUGAGUAGCUGGAACUAUAGGCACCCCCAACUGUGCCCAGCACUGGAUUCUCUUUAUUUUUUUAUUUAUUGUGUUUAUUUAUUUUUUGGAGAUGGAGUUUCGCGCUUGUCACCCAGGCUGGAGUGCAAUGGCGUGAUCUUGGCUCACUGCAGCUUCCGCCUCCUGGGUUCAAGUGAUUCUCCUGCCUCAGCCUCCCGAGUAGCUGGGAUUAAAGGCAUGUGCCACUACGCCUGGCUAAUUUUUGUAUUAUUAGUAGAGACAGAGUUUUAGCAUCUUGGCCAGGCUGGUCCUGAACUCCUGACCUCAGGUGAUCCACCCACCUCCUGACCUCAGGUGAUCCACCCACCUCGGUCUCUCAGAGUGCUGGGAUUACAGAUAUGAGCCACCGUACCCAGCCCUGGAUUCUCUAUAAAUCAGGCAUAUUUAAGUUACUUCUUAGAAAAGAUCCCAUGCUCUGUGAUUCUCAACAUUAGAUCUUAACUGAGUGCUUGUUUGGGCACUUAAACAGAUGAAGAAAAACUUCUUGGCUGGGCUUGGUAGUUCAGUAUCUCAUCUGUAUUGUGGGCUUAAUAGGUAUUGGUGGGCCAUCCUGGGAACGUACCAUUUAGAAAAUGAUCUAUGGCAAAAUGGGCUUCUAAGGUCAAAGCCAGAUUAUAUGAACUUUUGGAAUAAGGCCUGUUUUUUCUUUGAGUGCUGCUAACUGCUGGCCAGGGAUGUCCAAUCUUUUGUCUUCUCUGGGCCAUGUUGAAAGAAUUGUCUUGGACCACACAUGAAAUACACUUGAAGAAAUUUAUGAAUUUGUGUUGGGCUGCAUUGAAAGCCAUCCUGGGCUAUGGGUUAGAGAAGCUUGGUUUAUGGAUACCUAGGAAGGAAAAAUGAAUUCUCUGCCUUUCAUAAUUACUAAACUGUGGAAUUCAUAGGAGGAAGACAUUGAUUCUAUACAGGCAGGAUAAAAGCUGAUUAAUCCAGAUAAUUGAAGAGUUUCUACACACUCACUGUUCUUAGUUUUUAAAAUAACCUUAGGUUUAGACCAUAUCUAGAGAUUGAUAUGUUUGGUGGCUCUUAAGACAUUGUUGACUGUCUUUGCUAAUGGCAGGAAUGUAAGUCAAGAACUCUUGUAAUCGAAUUAUCUAAUAUUUUUAUUAAAACUGCAUAUAUAGUUGAAAACAAAUUGUUAUUUUAAAAUUGUUUUUUUAAAAUUGAUAUUUUAAAGCUUCAAGUAAAAGCUACCAUUAUUUGCUAAAAAAAAGAAACAUUCCUCUUCCCCAAACAAAUCCAAGAAGCAAAGCAAGAAGUGAAAAGAUUUGACUUUUUAAAGUGAAUUUGUAAAUUGGAUGCGGUGGCUCACCUGUAAUCCCAGCUACUUGGGAGGCUGAGGUGGGAGGAUGACUUGAGGCCAGAUGUUUGAGACCAUCCCAGGCAACAUAGCAAGACUCCAUUUCUAAAAAGAAGUAAAGUAAAUUUAUGUGCAACUCAUAAAUUCUGUGUUGAGAUAAAAACUGAAGUUACAAUUUGACUCUGGAAUGUUUAGUUAGUACUAUACAUCUUUUGAGUCUAAUUGACAGGGUGAGUUUUGUUUUGUUAUUUUGAGAUAAGAGUCACUAUUUUGCCCAGGCUGGCCUGGAACUCCUGGGCUCAGGCGAUCACUUCAGUCUCUGGAGUAGCUGGGAUUACCGCUUCAGAAGUGAUUUUGACAAGUUAUUCUGGAACUGUGUUGGAGAAGUUUAAAAAAGGUUGGGGUGGGAGUCGAAAUCAAACUAGUUUUACCAUACCAGGAUCUUUUUGUAGCACAUUUGAGAUGUAAACAUGUUUCCUUUUGAAAUUUGGUAGAAUAGUUAUAUUAUUUUUCCCAAUGCUAUGUGAUUAAAAACACAAGGCUCAAAUUUAUUUUUAAGGCUUGAUUAAAACCUCUUGUUUCUAUGGAAGAAAAGUUAUUAAAUUGAAAGGGGGCUUUAGAAAUUUUAAUUCCAAGAUUGCUUUAAGAAGAGAGAGGCAAGUCAAAUUGGAUAUGGGCCUCACAGAAUUGACCUUGCUACUUCCUGGGUCUGGGAAACUGAGGGGGCUAUGUUGCAUUGGGGCGGGGCGGAAGCCUGGUAGGAGCUAGAAGUGAAACUGGAAGUGCCUUAAAAAAGCACAUCGUUGUGUUAGGCUGAGUCAAGCUGGAAUGAGCAGUGAGACAGUACAAUUCUUAGGCAUAAAUAUGUACGUAGUUCACCUGUAGAUUUGCUGGAAGAGCCGACAUGUUUGCAGUACCACAGACCAGAGAAGUCUCAGUGGAGGAAAAUGAGAGAGAAGCAAAGGGAGAGAUGGAGUUAGGGGCCUUCGGGUUCAGAUUUUGAAAUAAAAUCUAUGAGUCUUUGAGGGAGGCAGCAGGAAGUUAAAGGUGGAAUACUGGAAAUAGUUUUCCUUCCUCCAUGCUGUAUGGAGAUGGGGGCUGCUGCAUGGAAGUGGGGGCUAGAUGUUGGUGAAGGUGUCCUUGUUCGAGCAGAGAAGGUAGUGUUGGUGCUUCUUUUCAGUGCCAGUCCAUCCAUCACGACCACAUUUGUCAUGAUGACAGUGACAAGUCCUCCUGUCAGGCGCCAGAGAGGAAGAAGGGAUCGUCUGUCUCGACAUAAUUCCAUUAGUCAAGAUGAAAACUAUCACCAUCUCCCUUACGCACAGCAGCAAGCAAUAGAGGAGCCUCGAGCCUUCCACCCUCCGAAUGUAUCUCCCCGUCUGCUACAUCCUGCUGCUCAUCCACCCCAGCAGAAUGCAGUCAUGGUUGACAUACAUGAUCAGCUCCAUCAAGGAACAGUCCCUGUUUCUUACACAGUAACAACAGUGGCACCACAUGGGAUUCCACUCUGCACAGGCCAGCACAUCCCUGCUUGUAGUACACAGCAGGUCCCAGGAUGCUCUGUGGUUUUCAGUGGACAGCACCUCCCUGUCUGUAGUGUGCCUCCUCCAAUGCUUCAGGCAUGUUCAGUUCAGCACUUACCAGUACCAUAUGCUGCAUUCCCACCCCUUAUUUCUAGUGAUCCAUUUCUUAUACAUCCUCCUCACCUUUCUCCCCAUCAUCCUCCUCAUUUGCCACCACCAGGCCAGUUUGUCCCUUUCCAAACACAGCAAUCACGAUCGCCUCUGCAAAGGAUAGAAAAUGAAGUGGAACUCUUAGGAGAACAUCUUCCAGUAGGAGGUUUUACUUACCCUCCAUCAGCCCACCCCCCAACAUUACCUCCAUCAGCUCCCUUGCAGUUCUUAACACAUGAUCCUUUGCAUCAGGAGGUGUCCUUUGGAGUACCUUAUCCUCCAUUUAUGCCUCGGAGGCUUACAGGACGUAGUAGAUACCGAUCCCAGCAGCCAAUACCACCUCCCCCUUAUCAUCCCAGCUUACUGCCAUAUGUGUUAUCAAUGCUUCCAGUGCCACCUGCAGUGGGCCCAACUUUCAGCUUUGAAUUAGAUGUAGAAGAUGGAGAAGUAGAAAAUUACGAGGCCCUGUUAAACCUGGCAGAGCGACUGGGAGAGGCAAAGCCUCGUGGACUGACUAAAGCAGAUAUUGAACAACUUCCUUCUUAUCGGUUCAAUCCUAACAACCACCAGUCAGAACAGACUUUGUGUGUAGUAUGCAUGUGUGAUUUUGAGUCAAGGCAGCUACUUAGAGUCUUACCCUGUAACCACGAGUUCCAUGCCAAGUGUGUUGACAAAUGGCUUAAGGCAAAUCGUACUUGCCCAAUUUGCCGAGCUGAUGCUUCAGAAGUGCAUCGGGAUUCAGAAUGACCAACCUAAGAAGCACAAAUUUAGUUUGGGUGUUCCUCAUCACAUGUAUAUACGGACUAUCCAUUGAACUUAAUCUGUGUGGCUUCCAGCCCUCCCUUUACCAAAAGGGUCAAUGGACCUUUCUUUGCACUGUGUGACUUAAUCAACUAUAAAAGCUUACAAUUAGUCUUCACAGUUAUGGGAUUGUUAUACUAACCGUGUGAUUGGAACUCCAAAGACUUUUUCUUUAGCUUAAUUUUGUGUGUGCACUAACAUUCCCUGGUUUUUGUGUGAUCAUUCCGAGUGUUGCUGCAAGAUUACAGUGGACGUGAUCUUUUAGCAUGUGCUUUUAUAAAAAGUGGUAGCUACAGAUGAUAUAGCAAUCUACCUUAUAUAGAGCCUUCAGAAACUGUGAGUGGAAAUGAAUGCGCAGCGUAUGACUGUUGGUGAUAAGUGUAUCUGUGUGAGUGUGUGCAACUACUUGUGUGAGGGCAUGGUAGCUAACGUGUGUAUGAGAUCCUAUAUACCAGCAUGUACCAAGAAUGUGUGUGUAGUUUUAAUUAUGCUGCAAUGUAUAAUCUGGUGUGUUAUUUAAACAGCACUAGUACUGUACACUGGUUUUUUUCCCUUGUGUUUGCUGUUGCACACUGAUUGCUGAGGGUGCAUCAAUUACAAGCAUUGAAUACUCCAUCCCCUUCCCUCCCAGUGAAUGGAAUGAGAAAAGCCUUCUUCCUUUGCUUCAGGCAGCUGUCACCUUCUCUUUAUUGGUGGUCCUAAGUGGGUCACUUAAGAAAAAAAAGUGUAACAAAUUCUCGCUCCAUGAACCUGGUUUUUUUUUAUUCUGUUGUGGAAAUUUUUAAAUCUCCAACUUGCUGUUUCCAAAAAGAAGGUGCAAUAUCAUAUAUCAUCAGUUAGCAAUAUUAGCAUUUCAAUCAGUGAUUUGAAUGUUGAUACUUUUUUUUCCUUUACAUUUCCAGUAAGUUUCUUACAGAAAGUACCUGUGAUUUUUUUUAAUGUUUAGAUUUGUAGUCUAGUCUAUUCUGAAGAUAUUUGAUUAAUAUAUUUCUAAGAAGACCACUAGUCCCAUGAAGUCUCACCUUGUUGACUUCCACCAGAACAAAACCUGUUAAUUCAGCUUGACUUCUCAUAUGUGUUCUGUGUUCAAGCUCCUGUGGGCAACUCAAUUGUUUUAAGAAAACUCUAUUUCUGUUCAUAUUAAUUCACUUGCCAGACUCCAAUUCUGAAAGUUGUCUAGUUCUUCCUUCAUCACACGUGCUUCUCAUCGAAACCCUGGUUUCAGGAUGGAUCAAGUGCUGUUACAGCUCAUGUUCCUUAGACCUGAUUUGUUUUGAUAUUUUACUGCCUUUCCUUUUAAUUUUUGUUUGAAUGAGAAAAGUUUAAUACAACAGGUGUCCAGAAUACUUGCAGUAUAAAUGAAGAUUUGGUUUUUGUAUAAAAAAAUAAUGCUGUUAAACAGGAGUUGACCUUCAUUUAGUUGAUGUAAUACAUAGCUGUAUGGGGUUUUUUUUAGUAAGUUCUUUGAGCAUAAUUCACUUUAAAGUCAUUUUUCCAGCAAUGUUUAAAUUACUUUCUCAUUCUUUUAGUGUAUUCAACAUUGUCUGCCUCUUCCUGCAGUUGAUGUAAUUGCUUUGUUUGCAAUAGCACAAGCUGCAUUAUUCCAGUCAGGACUGUGAUAACUUGCUGCCAGCCCCACUCAACUUUCAGUUGGCUCUGUGUCAGUUUUCCAUUCAGUGUUAACUACUUGUUACUGCCAUGCUGCUUGCCCUCCCUUGAAGUGUCUAUAAGCUCAUCACAGCCUAGAGUUAAGUAAAGUCAAUUCACAGAAGCACAAUUUUGCCCUUUGCGAGACAUUGUUGCCUCUAUCUAGUCCUACAAGUAGGGUUUUGCAUACUGUGUUUGCCCCUAGGGUUGUCAGUGCAUCAGAAAUACUUCUAAAUAGUGGUAAAAAUGCACAUGGUUAAUGCACAUGUUACUUUUAAAUCAUUAGGAUAUCCCUCACCUGUUCCUGAUGAAUAAAAAGUGUGUUAAAGACCAAAAUUCUUGGCAUAAUAAUCAGCUACAUACAAAUCACAUAUAGUUUAAUCUUUUUUAAUGAAAAAAAAUCAUGUUUAAAAUGGCAAAAGCCCAUCUUAUACACUUUUAUAUAGCUGCAAAAAAUUUAUAUCUGUACAGAUCUAACACUACGACACUCAGUAUUCAUUUUAUUGAAGCAUGCAAGUAAAGCACUUUUUCUAAUUUAUAUAGAGGUAUCUAAUUAACACAGCACAUUGUACUAAUGACUAGGAGUAGCAGCUUUUUCUUCUCUCCCUCUAUGAAUUCUUAUAAUGUCCCUUUUUCUGUAAGUUUUUGAGAGGCAAUUGGCAAUUUAGGAGGCAGCAGGGUCUGUUUUGGUCAAAUCUUGAAUUUCGUUGUUGCACUCUAGUGACUGAUCUUUGGGAAUGUCUUGUCUUUGCAUGGGGCUCAUAGAGAUGUGUGCAGACUUGCUUAUUGUGGUUAGUGUGUAUCAGGAACACACACACAGGUGUUCUGACCAGCUCAGGCUUGCCACAGUGAGCAACUCUGUGGCUAGCAAAAGAGAAGUUUAUUUGUGCCCAGCCAUUGGUCACCUUGGGUGAUGCACCAGAUAGCAGGCAGAUGUUGGUUCAUUGGCCUUCGUCCUCUUUCCUCCUAAAAUAAUAUUGGCUUUACCAUCUUAACUCAGCUGUGGGUUUUUUGUGGGUUCUUGUUUGUUUUUUGGCAUGAAUUGUCAUCUUUGGUGUUUUUUUAACCCCCAGCCCCUCAAAAAAAUAAGGCCUCCAGGUAUCAAGAUCUCAUAUUAGGAUUUUCUGUCCUUAAUUUUUUGAGCAAAAUCUGGAAAAUGUGAAAGCAUAUUUAGAUUUUAUAUACUAUCUGAAAUGUGAUUUGUUAAGAUUCUUAAAUUUGGGCCUCUUAGAAUAAUUUUGAAUGAGAUCUACCGACUCACUUGUGAGAAUAUUUUUCACAGAUUAUCUUUGGGCCUUUUCAUUAGAAAGCUGUUUGUUUGUCCCCCUGUUGGUACAUUUGGUUACCUCAUUUUGCCGUUUCAGAUUGUGAAAGCUCACAGGGGUGUUUUUUGGAAUCAUUUGCUGAGUCAUUUUCUCAAAUCAUAUUCCAUUGUAUCAGUUAACAUAUAGUUUUAAAUGUAUGUAUUAUAAAUAUCUGUAACCAAAUCAUUUGAAGGCUUGAUAAAUUUUUAACAAAGUUUGUACAUUUUUUAUGAAAGUUACUAGUAAUGCUUUACUAAGUAGUGCAAUGAAUUUUUAUUUUUAAUCCCUGUGCCCAAUUUUGGAGUUGAGAGGGUUGUUGGUAAUAAAUGUAUGAUGUACACUUAAAA